CGCCCCCGGGCCGGGCAGAUGCGGUUUCCUCCCGACUCGCGAUCAAAAUGGGUGAGUAGCGCAGAGCUCGCCUCUUGGAGGCCUCUUUCUGAAGGCGGAGGACGCGGGGCGGCUCGUUCAUGGGCCGGGUGGCUCCGCAGGGUAGACGAAGGCUGCAGCGUCCGCACUGGGCUGGGAACGACUUGCAAGGGGAGCCCAGCUGGCGCCCCGGAGCCAGCCAGCUGGCUAGCGGCCCCACCAGCGCAAGUGCCCCGCACCUGCCCGCCUGCUCCGAGCGUCAAGAGAAGGCGGCAUUUCGCAUGGGUAAAAUCCGCGCGGGGACGCCGGGAGAAUGUUGUUGCUCUUGCCGUUCGGCCCAUUGUACAGACGCAGCCAGCGAGGCUCGCAGAGGUCAGGGAUGCACGUAGGACUGGCCCGCACCUUGCAGCCACGGAAAGAUCCGCCUGGCCCGCGGCCCCUCCACGCCUCCGAGGUCGAGACAGUGACAUAAGUCAACUCUCAAGCCCAGGGCGUCUCUCCACUCUGCCUAGACGUCCACUCCGUCUGCCUGCAGCUACGGCUCUGUGCGUCCCGCUUCGACUCCCUCUGCUUUCCUUCCCAGCUUCUCGCCUCCAGACUGUUCCGGCUCCGCCGCCUGAAAUUACCUGCUCUGGGGGAGGCGCGGCGCGCGGCCUCAUGACGGAACUACAACUCCCAUGAGGCGCUGGGCCCACGCAGGCGCGGCGCGGCUGAAGUCGCCGCGCCGGAAUCCCAUUGGCAGGGCCGGCUCUGAGGCGGGAGCCCUGAUUGGCUGAGGGGUCUGAGGCGACAGAUUCCGGAAAGGGGAAGAGCAGCCAACAUGGCGGCGGAACGCGGCGCGGGGCAGCAACAGUCGCAGGAGAUGAUGGAGGAAGAACAUGAGCUGCCUGUGGACAUGGAAACCAUCAACCUGGACAGAGAUGCAGAGGAUGUUGAUUUGAAUCACUAUCGCAUAGGGAAGAUUGAAGGAUUUGAGGUACUGAAGAAAGUGAAGACUCUCUGCCUCCGCCAAAAUUUAAUUAAAUGCAUUGAGAAUCUGGAGGAGCUACAGAGUCUUCGAGAGCUGGAUCUUUACGACAACCAGAUCAAGAAGAUUGAGAAUCUGGAGGCGCUAACAGAGCUGGAGAUUCUAGAUAUUUCUUUUAAUCUGCUGAGAAACAUCGAAGGGGUUGACAAGUUGACACGACUGAAAAAACUCUUCUUGGUCAACAAUAAAAUCAGUAAAAUUGAGAACUUAAGCAACUUACAUCAACUACAGAUGCUAGAGCUGGGAUCUAACCGCAUCCGGGCAAUCGAAAAUAUCGACACCUUAACCAACCUGGAGAGUUUGUUUUUGGGGAAAAACAAAAUUACUAAACUUCAGAACCUGGAUGCGCUCACCAACCUGACAGUCCUCAGUAUGCAGAGCAACCGGCUGACCAAGAUCGAGGGUCUGCAGAACCUGGUGAACCUGCGGGAGCUGUACCUUAGCCACAAUGGCAUCGAGGUCAUCGAGGGCCUGGAGAACAAUAACAAACUCACGAUGUUGGACAUUGCAUCAAAUAGAAUCAAAAAGAUUGAAAAUAUCAGCCAUCUAACAGAGCUGCAAGAGUUCUGGAUGAACGACAAUCUCCUUGAGAGCUGGAGCGACCUCGACGAGCUGAAGGGAGCCAGGAGCCUGGAGACAGUGUACCUGGAGCGGAACCCCUUGCAGAAGGACCCCCAGUACCGGCGGAAGGUCAUGCUCGCCCUCCCCUCCGUGCGGCAGAUCGAUGCCACGUUCGUCAGGUUCUGAGUCCUUCUUGGCUCCUCAUGUGGUCCCUCUCCUCGGAAGAACUGCCCAGCCACGGGUUUUUAACCCACCUGUUGCUCCUGAGGUCGUCACUAUAUCAACAGUCACAAACCCAAUGGCAAUAAAGGCACUGACGAUAGCUGGCGCGCGCGACGUCACACACCAUUUUCAGAUGCCGUUGCAAUUAAAUCUUGCCACACUGUCCUCCUGGGUGAUUGUUGACAGUUAUUGUAGCCACAGAGAGAACAUAAGACACGUUGCGUUCAUUCGCUAGAAAUCCCUGUUUCCUUCUCUCAGAAGGCAGUCACAGUCCCUACCUGAGUCGUGUGAAACACAGGGCCUGAGAGUGCUUUACAGGCAUUCACGUGCUGUCCGAGUGGCAUUCGGGGGCUGGCCUAGCUGGCCCUAGUCCUGGUGUGCAGGGUUCAGGCAGUCUUGACCUGCAACAACCGAGGUUUUUUAGUCUUUUAACCCAGCCAUUUUCAAUUUUUUAAAAAUUAGGUAAGUUAAAAAAGCUGGGUAAAAGCUGACUCAGCCCUGUGUGCUUGUGUUCCUUAGAGCUCUCCUUCAAAGAGCGCCGGGCAGGGCUGACUGUUUUCACGUGUGCCCGUCAGUUCUCGCCACAUCCCUUGCCUGUGGGUGAAAGCUCAGGUGUGGGGAGGGUGUCCUGUGUCCCACACGGUGCUGUGCUGCUGCCAGAAUACGAGUCCCAUUGAGCCUCUCCAAAGACGGCCUCCAAGGAUCUGAACUCUUGGCCACUGGUAUAGUGGCCUCCUGUUCUCACCCCAUUGUUAUUUUGGCUUUUUUAAUAUAAAAUGUACAUUGACAGA